AGAGGCCCAGGAAAGAGAGAGAAGACCAACCAAGGGGUGGCUGGAGUCCCAAGGCCAUGAACUUUCAGGAAAAUGUGACCCUGGCCAUGGCCUUGUUCACCAUCCUGACCUCCAUCUAUUUCUUCAACAAGGCUCAGCAGUGAGAAGACACAGGACCUCCCCGCACAAGAGCCCUGCCUCUCCCUCUGCCAUCGCUCUGAGGCCAGAUAAAUGUAACUGAAUCCGCA